AUCCACGCCAGGCCAGAAGGACCAGGGGCUGGAAACUCGCCUUCAGGGCUCCUAAGCUGCUGCGGAGCUAGACGGCGGGCUGUGGGUGGGGAGGAGACUAGAAUAUUCUGAGACGUGGUAGGGUGGGAGUUAGGAGAGGUAACCUGGAGUUGUUGCCCAAGAUGCAGCUCAGCUCCAGUGGCCACACCAAGAAGGCUUGAGACCGGGGGCAGAACCAGGGGGAUUUUGUGGUGGCUGGGGGCCUGCAUUUGAGUUCCUUGACCAGCAGGAGGGCUUGGAUUUAGGGAGGCUCUAAUCGCCUGCACGAAGAACCCCGCGCUGUCUGGCCCACCCUUCACAGUAUCCGACCGGGGCGUCCUGAACCGCCGCCAGCUCUAUCUGACCACCUCGGCGCGGGACUUUCGGUUCUAUCCCAAGACGGAGCCGUCCGGAUACCCCCGCAAGGACUACCUGACCUACUGGAGCUUAGAAGAGACGCCCCAACUCUGGAGUCACGACCCGCAGCGGCAGCCCUGUCUCUGCUCUUCCAGGCCGCCUCGAGCGCCGCACGGCGGGCCAUGUCUCCGGCUCAGGAAACCUACAGCUCCUCGCCGCACCCGCUCCGCCGGCUCGACCGCUUCCGCCCGCUGGAGGCGACUUGGGGUGGCCCCCACUGGAAGCCCCUGCCGGGCAUACACAGCGUCCCGAAAGCCUACAGCACCGAGAACUCCCGCUCAGGCCGCUGUAAGCCGGGGCUAGUGGGAGCCUGCCGGGCCAGCCCCACCCCAGACACGCCCCCUGGCGUGGGGGCGGAGCAGAGCUCUGGGCAGCCGCUCACUACGCGGUGUCGGACCUAGGUGGGCUCGCACUCAUUAAGUCUAUCCGCAGUGUGGGGACAGGACUAGCCCAGACACGCCCACUCAGCUGCGGCUGGAUCGCGGGGAAGGGACUAAGUCCAGACAAUGUCCUCCGAGGCUGCGGCCCCGCGGGCAGGACACACCUCCUGCGGGCCUAUUCAAUAAUCAGUUAAAUCACCUGAAGCACACGCAUUUCCGGGGACCGCUCCGGGCAUCCUGGCUUGAGGGUAGGGUGGGCGGAGGUUCCUAAGGGAGAGGUGGGGCUCGGGCUGAAUCCCUCGUUGGGGGGCAUCUGGGUCAAGUGGCUUCCCUGGCAGCACAGUCACGGGGAGACCCUCUCUCACUGGGCAGAAGCUAAGUCCGAAGCCGCGCCCCUCCUGUUAGGUUGGACUGUGGUGCAGGAAUGGCUCAAGUAGAGGAGGGUUGAGGCUUCAGUCCAGCACCUUUCUCGGGUCACGGCCUCCUCCUGGUUCCCAAGACCCCACCAUAGGCAGAGGCAGGCCUUCCUACACCCUACUCUCUGUGCCUCCAGCCUCGACUAGUCCCUAGCACUCGACGACUGAGUCUCAGAGGUCACUUCACCGUGGUCUCCGCCUCAUCCUUGGCGCUAGACCACUGAGGGGAGAGGACUGGGGUGCUCCGCUGAGCCACUCCUGUGCCUCCCUGGCCUUGUCUACUUCUCGCCCCCCGAAGGGUUAGUGUCCAGCUCACUCCAGCAUCCUACAACCUCCUGGUGGCCUUGACGCCCCCACAAACCCGAGGUAUAAAGCCAGGUACACCAGGCAGGGGACGCACCAAGGAUGGAGAUGUUCCAGGGGCUGCUGCUGUUGCUGCUGCUGAGCAUGGGCGGGACAUGGGCAUCCAGGGAGAUGCUUCGGCCACGGUGCCGCCCCAUCAAUGCCACCCUGGCUGUGGAGAAGGAGGGCUGCCCCGUGUGCAUCACCGUCAACACCACCAUCUGUGCCGGCUACUGCCCCACCAUGACCCGCGUGCUGCAGGGGGUCCUGCCGGCCCUGCCUCAGGUGGUGUGCAACUACCGCGAUGUGCGCUUCGAGUCCAUCCGGCUCCCUGGCUGCCCGCGCGGCGUGAACCCCGUGGUCUCCUACGCCGUGGCUCUCAGCUGUCAAUGUGCACUCUGCCGCCGCAGCACCACUGACUGCGGGGGUCCCAAGGACCACCCCUUGACCUGUGAUGACCCCCGCUUCCAGGCCUCCUCUUCCUCAAAGGCCCCUCCCCCCAGCCUUCCAAGUCCAUCCCGACUCCCGGGGCCCUCAGACACCCCGAUCCUCCCACAAUAAAGGCUUCUCAAUCCGCA